GGCACCCCCCUUUCUCUGCCCCCCGCCCCCAAGCCGCGGCCAUGGACCUGGCGGAUCCGGCCUGCCCUGGCCCAGCUCAACACCUGAUUUCGGCAAGGUGACCGUUCUGGAUGCUAGAGUGAGUGUGCCCACCUGCGUAAGGGGGCAGAGACAGCCUGCCGGGGCUUCUCUUCCUUGUUCCCAGGGCCAGAUGUCAGAGGCCAUGGACCAGCCAGCUGGGGGUCCUGGAAACCCAAGGCCAGGAGAGGGUGAUGAUGGCAGCAUGGAGCCAGGCACCUGCCAGGAGCUUCUGCACCGACUGCGGGAGCUGGAGGCAGAGAACUCGGCACUUGCCCAGGCCAACGAAAACCAGCGGGAGACUUAUGAGCGCUGUCUGGACGAGGUUGCCAACCAUGUGGUACAGGCGUUGCUGAACCAGAAGGACCUGCGAGAGGAGUGCAUCAAGCUGAAGAAGAGAGUGUUUGACCUGGAACGGCAGAACCAGAUGCUGAGUGCCCUGUUUCAGCAGAAACUCCAGCUCACGACAGGCUCGCUCCCUCAGAUCCCACUCACUCCACUCCAGCCACCAUCAGAGCCACCAGCCUCCCCCUCCCUGAGCUCCACUGAGGGACCGGCUGCCCCGCUGCCUCUGGGGCACUGUGCUGGGCAGAGAGAGGUAUGUUGGGAGCAGCAGCUGAGGCCAGGAGGCCCAGGCCCCCCAGCCGCCCCACCCCCAGCGCUGGAUGCCCUAUCCCCGUUCCUUCGGAAGAAGGCCCAGAUUCUGGAGGUGCUGAGAGCCCUGGAAGAGACUGACCCCUUGCUUCUCUGCUCACCUGCCACCCCCUGGCGGCCUCCAGGCCAGGGGCCUGGCUCCCCAGAGCCCAUCAACGGCGAGCUGUGUGGCCCGCCUCAGCCUGAACCCUCACCCUGGGCGCCCUGCCUGCUGCUAGGCCCUGGCAACCUGGGAGGCCUGCUGCACUGGGAGCGCCUCUUGGGGGGUCUGGGAGGGGAAGAGGACACUGGGCGGCCCUGGGGUCCUAGCAGGGGACCUCCUCAGGCCCAGGGCACCAGCUCUGGCCCAAACUGUGCCCCAGGCAGCAGCUCCUCCUCCUCUUCUGAUGAGGCAGGUGACCCCAAUGAGGCACCCAGCCCCGACACCCUGCUCGGUGCCCUGGCCCGCAGACAGUUGAACCUGGGCCAGCUCCUUGAGGACACAGAGUCUUACCUACAGGCCUUCCUGGCCGGGGCUGCAGGCCCACUCAAUGGGGACCACCCAGGUCCUGGGCAGUCAUCCUCCCCAGACCAGGCGCCCCCACAGCUGUCUAAGUCCAAAGGCCUCCCCAAGUCAGCUUGGGGUGGGGGUACCCCAGAGGCCCACAGGCCAGGCUUCGGUGCUACCUCAGAGGGCCAGGGGCCCCUCCCCUUCCUUAGCAUGUUCAUGGGUGCUGGGGAUGCCCCACUGGGCUCUCGGCCUGGCCACCCCCAUUCCUCAUCUCAGGUGAAAAGCAAGCUCCAAAUUGGCCCCCCUUCUCCUGGGGAAGCUCAGGGACCCCUUCUGCCCUCUCCAGCUAGGGGUCUCAAGUUUCUAAAGCUGCCUCCAACCUCGGAGAAGAGCCCCAGCCCAGGAGGCCCGCAGCUCAGUCCCCAGCUCCCCCGGAACUCGCGAAUCCCCUGUCGGAACAGUGGCUCAGACGGCAGCCCCUCCCCACUGUUGGCCCGAAGGGGUCUGGGUGGAGGAGAGCUGUCCCCAGAGGGGGCGCAAGGCCUGCCCACCAGCCCUUCACCCUGCUACACAACCCCAGACUCCACACAGCUCAGACCCCCGCAGUCAGCCUUGUCCACCACGCUGUCCCCAGGCCCAGUGGUGUCUCCCUGCUAUGAGAACAUUCUGGACCUUUCUCGGAGCACCUUUAGGGGGCCUUCCCCAGAGCCACCUCCAUCCCCACUGCAGGUGCCCACCUACCCACAGCUAACUCUGGAGGUACCACAGGCCCCUGAGGUCCUCAGAAGCCCUGGAGUACCCCCCAGUCCUUGCCUCCCAGAAUCGUACCCCUAUGGGAGCCCCCAAGAGAAGAGUUUGGACAAGGCAGGCUCGGAGUCUCCCCAUCCCGGCCGCAGGACCCCAGGCAACUCAUCCAAGAAGCCCAGCCAGGGGUCAGGACGGCGACCUGGGGAUCCUGGCAGCACACCUCUGCGGGACAGACUGGCGGCCCUGGGGAAGCUGAAGACAGGCCCCGAGGGGGCCCUGGGCUCAGAGAAGAAUGGGGUGCCAGCCAGGCCUGGCACCGAAAAGACCCGGGGACCUGGGAAGUCAGGGGAGAGUGCUGGAGACAUGGUGCCCUCCAUCCACAGGCCACUGGAGCAGCUAGAAGCCAAGGGGGGGAUACGGGGGGCAGUGGCCUUGGGCACAAACAGCCUGAAGCAGCAGGAACCUGGACUUAUGGGGGAUCCCGGGGCCCGAGUCUACUCCUCUCACUCCAUGGGGGCCCGGGUGGACCUGGAGCCUGUCUCACCAAGGAGCUGCCUCACCAAAGUGGAGCUGGCCAAGAGCCGGCUGGCAGGGGCCCUGUGCCCCCAGGUACCCCGUACCCCUGCCAAAGUGCCAACCUCAGCCCCAAGCCUGGGCAAGCCCAAUAAGAGCCCUCACAGCAGCCCCACCAAGCUCCCUUCCAAGUCACCAACCAAGGUGGUGCCUCGACCUGGGGCUCCGCUAGUCACCAAGGAGUCCCCCAAGCCUGACAAAGGGAAGGGCCCUCCCUGGGCAGACUGUGGUAGUACCACGGCCCAGUCCACACCCCUAGUACCUGGCCCCACUGACCCAAGUCAGGGCCCUGAGGGGCUGGCCCCACACUCAGCCAUCGAGGAGAAGGUGAUGAAGGGCAUUGAGGAGAACGUGCUGCGGCUCCAGGGCCAGGAGCGAGCCCCUGGCGCCGAGGUCAAGCACCGCAACACCAGCAGCAUCGCCAGCUGGUUCGGCCUUAAGAAGAGCAAGCUGCCAGCGCUGAACCGCCGCACAGAGGCCACCAAGAACAAGGAGGGGGCUGGCGGGGGCUCCCCGCUCCGGAGGGAAGUCAAGAUGGAAGCCCGGAAGCUGGAGGCCGAGAGCCUCAACAUCUCCAAGCUGAUGGCCAAGGCGGAAGACCUGCGUCGGGCACUGGAAGAGGAGAAGGCCUACCUAAGCAGCCGGGCCCGGCCACGGCCUGGUGGCCCAGCCCCAGGGCCCAACACGGGGCUGGGGCAGGUGCAGGGCCAGCUGGCUGGCAUGUACCAAGGUGCAGACACCUUCAUGCAGCAGCUGCUAAACAGGGUGGAUGGCAAGGAGCUGCCAUCCAAGAGCUGGCGGGAGCCCAAGCCUGAGUACGGGGAUUUCCAGCCGGUGUCUUCUGACCCCAAGAGCCCCUGGCCAGCCUGUGGGCCCCGGAAUGGCCUGGUGGGCCCUCUUCAGGGCUGCGGAAAACCUCCUGGAAAGCCGAGCAGCGAGCCAGGGAGGCGGGAAGAGAUGCCCUCGGAGGACAGCCUGGCCGAGCCAGUGCCCACCUCACACUUCACAGCCUGUGGCUCCUUGACUCGAACCUUGGACAGUGGCAUUGGGACCUUCCCACCCCCAGACCAUGGUAGCAGUGGGACCCCCAGCAAGAAUCUUCCUAAGACCAAGCCACCGCGGCUGGAUCCCCCACCUGGGGUACCCCCAGCUCGGCCCCCACCCCUUACCAAAGUCCCCCGCCGCGCCCACACACUGGAGCGGGAGGUGCCAGGCAUAGAGGAGCUGCUGGUGAGUGGGCGGCACCCCAGCAUGCCAGCCUUCCCUGCACUGCUACCCGCUGCUCCGGGCCACCGGGGCCAUGAGACCUGUCCUGAUGAUCCCUGUGAAGACCCAGGCCCCACCCCUCCUGUCCAGCUGGCCAAGAACUGGACCUUCCCCAAUACUAGGGCAGCCGGCAGCUCCUCGGACCCUCUCAUGUGCCCACCCCGACAACUGGAGGGGCUGCCCAGGACCCCCAUGGUGAGAAUUGCAGCAGAGGAAAGGGAAAGGACUCGGGAGCAGGAGGGAGUGAUGUGGGGAGACCAGUUUCUCCAGUAAGGUACGGCCUGUGUGUCGCACAGUCUCAGUGCUGCACCCUCUGGGAGGAGGACCCCUGGGAUGCCCUGUGAGCGGCCCUCCCCACUGCCCUCCUUGCACUUCUCUCGUGGGGAAAGGUUUCUGUCCCUCCCCAGAACCUUGUAGGACUGUUCUCAGUUGUACCUCCAGCCUGUUUCCUCUGAAGUAUACCCCACCUUGGGCCCCCUCUGGAGCAGCCCCCCAUCAGGUGCACAGACGCCCCUCAGAGCUCAGUGCCUCUGAGGCUGGGCCGAAAGGUGGAGAGGAGCUUCCUCCCGAGCUGCCCCUCCUUUCCCAGGCCCUGCCCGUGGACCGGAAGCGAAGCCAGGAGCCCAGCCGCCCGUCCCCUACGCCCCAGGGCCCACCUUUCGGGGGUAGCCGCACCCCCAGCACUUCGGACAUGGCCGAGGAAGGCAGAGUGGCCAGCGGGGGCCCCCCAGGGCUGGAGACCUCGGAGUCUCUCAGUGACUCACUCUACGACUCGCUGUCCUCUUGUGGGAGUCAGGGCUGAGGGGCUGCGCCACGCCACGGCCCCGCUGGAGCUGGGGACCACAGACUGGACCGGCUCUCUUCAUGCCCAGCCCCCGGAGACGGGGACCCCUCCCUGAAGGGACCAAGGAGGCAGGUGGAUAAGAAGGUGAAAAGGGGGUCCCUGGCACACCCCACCACCCACUGCUUCGGCGGAUGAGAUGACCGUGCUCAGCUCAGGGAGAGACCCCGCCCUUGGUCCCUUCUCUCACCCAGAGUAAGGCUCUUCCUGGAAGGGACUGGGGGUUAAAGGCCACUGUGUCGCAGCCCUCCAGUCCCUACUUCAGGCUGAGCCAUCUUGUGGUGCUGGGCUUCCUGCCCACCAGCCGUGCCAUCUCUGCCCAACCCGGCUGCUCCUCUGCCCCGAAGCCCUCGCGAGGCCCUCCUGGAGGCCCCCGUGCUGGUGGAGUUUGGGGGCCAGGGGGACAAGUUGCCUUCUCUCUCUGCCCUGGUCCUCCCUGCUGUCUGGAUGGUGCUGCCCUCCUCUGCCCCAUGCCUUUGGGGUCUGUUCGUCCGUCUUUUUUGUUGUUGUUUUUAUAUAUUGAAGCGCCUGGCCCAGCCCCCAGCCCCCAGCCCCGCACUGCGGUUAAUUUAUGUGUUGUUUAAAAUGCGGCUGCUCUGCUUCCUGCCUCUGCUUCUGCCGUAUCCCUAAUAAAAUGUGGAGGCCCCC